CUCCUCAGCCUCCCAAAGUGCUGGUAUUACAGGUGUGAGCCACCCUGCCCAGCCUAGAUUACUUUCUUCUAGCCAGGAGUCUUCCCUGAUGGUUCAGAUAUAACGGAUGGGGUCUUUUGGAUGUGGCAUGCCUGGUGUCUUUGGAGGAACUUAUCUGUCAGGGCAGCUUUGCCAGACAUCUCCUGGGUGCCUGAGUUUGGGGGCUUCUCCCUUUGCCAAUGAAAUGGGUUAUUUAUUUAUGGAGUACAUCUGUGCCUAUUCCAUCUAUCCACCCAUCUACACACCCGCCCACCCAUCUAACAUUCCUUAAAUGCCUGCCAUACUCCAGGUACCACGUUAGGAGCUGAGGGUGCCAGAAGGAUGCCCUUGCCUUCAGAGAGCACCCAGUGCCAUAGGAGAGACAGACUGCAGAUGCCCCCAGAGGUCCAUGAGGCCAUGAUUUCCGUUAGAGUGUAGCAGGAGGGAGUGUAAUGUAAACAAAUAAUGAUAAGGCAGAAUGACACCUGCCGGUAUACACAGGGUUCUGAGAAGUGGCUUUAGGACUGGAUAUUGAAGGAGGUAGAACACUUUAGCUGAAGAGGAGGACAUAGCAACCAGCCAGGACAAGGAUGAGGACUACAGAGAGGGUGGGCCAGGGUGGGGAAGCAGCAAGGUGUGUUAGAGCUGCCAGAGUCUGCAAGAGUAGAUGGAGGAGAGCAGCUACAGAGGGGCUUGGAUGGUGGGCUGGGGGCCUGUGGGUCCUAUGAGGACUGGCCCUUUGCUCAUGAAGGAUGAGAAUCUCUUAGGGAAAAAAAAAAAUCCUACGCACUCAGCUUCCAUGCCCUGAGGGGUUUCCAGGCAUAUUAGCAGCAACUGAAGUGGGAGCUGAGGGGAGAGGGAGGUGAGGGGCUAUGUUGGAAUCAAAAAGGAGGAAGGGGGCACAUGCCACACUCUUGCACCCAAAGGUAGAGUGGGCAUGUGGCCCUUCCAGUGCCCUUUGUACCUCGUCCUCGCUCCACGUUCCCUGACCCAUGGUUUUGCUGCUCUUACAAGGCCUGUCCUCCCCUCUCUUCAUUCCCUGUCUCUGCCUUUGGUGUCUGGAGAGUGAGAAAGCUGACUCGUGUGCAGAAGUGAUGCUGGCCCUGAGUAAUUUCAGAAGAAGUGGGUAGAGAGGAGGGUGUGGGUAUCUGGAGGCCUGAAUUUCAACCCUGCUCCCCCAGACUUGCUGUAUGGCCUCAGGGCAGUCACUGUCCACUCUGGGCCUCAGGGUCUACGUCUUCAAUGAGGGCAUCUGAGACAAUACCCUCUGGGUCCUCUCUGGUUUGGGCAUCGUGCAAUGUCGAUGCCUUAGUGUCUUCUCCAAGCUUCCUUUCCCAGCUGUCUUCCUCCCCCAGGCUCCACCCCUGCCUCUCCCUCCUGCUCCAUCCGGCUGCAGUUGGGCAGGAGCGGGAGAGAACCACCUUCCCCUCCAGGGAGGGGAAGACCUCCUGGGGGAGACCAGGAACCUCAGUAUUUGCUUGACAGUUAUCUGAUGCUUGCCCGAAAAUCAGGGUUGAAAUGGCAUUCGUUCCAUUACAAGGCAGACCAUUAAGGCCAAUCUCAACAUAGAGAGCUUUGUCGUCCCCUGAGUGGUUUUUGGUUCUUAUUGUCAUGGACUUUGGUUCAAAUGAAAAUGUUCCAGAAAACUGCCUUCUCAUUCUGUAGCAUUUGAGAGGGGAAAUGAGAGAAUGCGUGCCCUCUUCGUGGUUCUUGGAGCAAGGUGGGGGUGGCCGAGGCCCUGGCCUGCUCAUGCCUGCACAGGAAACGGCUGCCACUCCCUUCAGGAAUGUCAGUUACACAGCAAGUACUGUAUGGACAAAUCACUGUCCAUCUCCUUCCAGUGCAUCCAACCAUUGAUUGUUUUUUUUUUGUUUUUUGUUUUUUUUUUUUCAAAGAGCUGCUGAGUGAAAAACCUCCUGGUCAGAGCAGUGAGGGCGAGAGAUUAAUUUUCACCCAUGAGCUCUGCUCUAAGGACAGCUUAGAGGCAGUUGCUGAGGCAGUUCAGAGGGGUGGAGCUGACCUGGAAGGGGUUUGAGGUCAGCGCUGGAGGUAGAAGGCUCAGCAGACAUGGUUCUCAGACAGAGGCUUGGCCAGAGGAUAAAGUGCUGCUAUAGCCAGUUAGGGGCAUGGGGAAAUGUCUACAUCCCUGCAGUUCUCCAAAAUAAGACAACUCCUACACAAUAAAACAACCAUAACUACCGCCCCCAUGUACACACACACGUGCACUCGUGCGUGCGCCUCUGCAAUAGAAUGAUUUUUCCAAAGGCCCGCUAGUUUCAAGCCCUAGUUCCGGAAUUCCAGUUGCCAAUCCUUCCAGCUUUUUUGUCAGAUUGUGUUGAAUCGACCCUUUCUUAACGAAGGCUUCUCCCGUAACCCAGUGUGUCCUGCCAACCUCGUUCUGAGCAGAGACCUCACUUCCUCUAUAGCAGCCCCUUAGCCCUCUGGUGCGGGACUGCCCUAAGCCCGAGCAGGCUGGGCUGUGGGGCCGCACGUGGGGCGCCUCUGAGGAUGCUGCGGCUGUGGUUCUGCUCUGGCUGUGGCGACAUCGCGUGGCCUAAUGCGGAACUGCAACUUGGUAGCGGACGGCCCCUCUCCCGAGCUACUGGCCCUUCUGCCUUUUUCUCUCUGUUGCUGUCUCUCUUCUCUUCUGCUUUUUCUCCUUCUCUUUUCCCUCUAGACCCGGCUUUGCAGCUGGAGAGGCUGGUCCGUUUGCCCCUGGGGAAACACUUUAUCAGGCCGAGCGAAAUGUUGUCUCAAGUCACAGAAAAUCCAUGCUUUGGGGGAUGGCCUUCGCCAGCCACAGCCAGAUUUCUUCGCGUGUUUCUUGAAAUCCAGAAGCCCAGACUCUGUAAGGUGAUUCGUGUCCUCGCCUUUGCUUAUCCGUACACCUGGGACUCCCUCCCCAUCUUCUACAGGCUAUUCCUGUUCCCAGGGGAGAGUGCACAAAAUGAAGCCACCUCGUACCACCAGAAGCACAUGAUCAUGACCCUCCUGGCCUCUUUCUUGUACUCUGCACAUCUGCCAGAACGCCUAGCCCCUGGACGCUUUGACUACAUCGGUCACAGUCACCAGCUGUUUCACGUGUGUGUGAUCCUGGCCACGCACAUGCAGAUGGAAGCCAUACUUCUGGACAAGACUCUGAGGAAGGAAUGGCUCCUGGCCACCUCCAAGCCCUUCUCUUUCUCUCAGAUAGCUGGAGCCAUACUUCUGUGCAUCAUCUUCAGCCUCAGCAACAUAAUUUAUUUCUCAGCUGCUCUGUAUCGGAUUCCCAAGCCAGAAUUACAUAAAAAAGAAACAUGACUCAGACCAUAAGCUUUUCAUGCCAGAUGUCAACAUUAAGCUGCAACAUCCUAACCACCAUAAGCCGGAGGUGGUUACAGCUUAUCAUGGCCUAAAAUAUUCAUAAUGGUUGGUGUCUUUUGAAUGAAUUCAUGUCAAAAAUGUUAUUCAGCUGGGGAAAUUUCUCUAAAUGUACACUGAUUCUGUGUGUGUGAUUUUAAAAGGAGAAUAUGGUUCAAGCAAGUCCUUGUUAAGGCAAACUAUUGAUAUUUCAUUAAUUUUAAAUUUACUUAAAAUGUGGUUUUAAAUUCUAUUUAAACAUUUGGAUUAAGCAUAUUACUCUGGAGCUUUGUAUUAUUCUUUAAAAAUGAAUCUUGCUUCAUUUGAUGAAUUUCAUGUCACAAAGCUUCUCUCAAGAGCUCUCGUAGUGGCCUGUCAACCACUUUCGGAGAAUGAGCCAGGUCAGUCACUGGGAGGACCUGUGAAAGAAAGUUGGUCACUGAGUGCCUUGGGGACUGGCAAAACAUUCCAGAAUGAAGAGAGCUGUCUGGGGAGAGCCCUUCUUCCCUUCUCCACCUAGUGAAGGGAGAACAGAAGGGGAGUCCUCUCUUCCCACAAGUCCAUUCUGCCUUCAAAGUGUAAGUUCUCAUGUCAUUAUGGAUUUGGAGUUUGUCAGUUUUUUUCUUAAAAGUCCACAGCGGGGUGUCAUGUGUUCUGUUAUGUUCUGUUUUCUGGUUGCCAGUUUGAUCUGCAAAGUAUUUUUCAGUGCAGGUAAAAUGUGUUAAACCAUAAGAGUUGACUGAGUUAAUCCCAAUUGGUUGUGCUCAUAUGCCACCUUUUAAACCAAUGGAAAUUGCUAUAUUUGGGGAUGUCAUACAUUUGAUAUUGCUUCAGCAUUUCAAAUAUGUUGCAAAAUUUAGUAUCCAUAUGCAUAAGAAGUUAAUCACCUUGCCAGUGGGGUGGUCACAUAUAGUGUUCUCAAGCUUUACUGUGAAUCAGAAACAUCCAGUAAGCUUGUGACAAAUGCAGACUCCUAGGGAAAACCAGGGGGUUCUGCUUCACUAGGUUAAAUGUAGGUUUUGUAGAGGAGAUCUGCACUGGAGCAAGUCUCCCAGAUGAUUCUAAUACAGGAGGGCCAGAGGCCAAACUUGAAGAACUGCUGGUGUUACAUGUUCCAAAAGGCAUUAGACCUAUCAGCUUUGUUUCGCCUGAUCUCAAGUUUUAGCAACUCACCAACUAAGGCGUAACCUCAUUUUAUGUUCCAGCGUUUUCUACUCUGAAUAGUUCUAAAACACUGAGCAUUUUCUCAUUUGUUGCAUUACUGAUUAAAGUUCAGUAUUUCAUGGUGUUUUCAGGGAACACAGAAAUGCGGAUGCAAAACAACUUUUGACAGAGGCCCAUCAAACCCAGAUCUGCACUUGGUAAUGACUUAGGGGGGCUUCCUCACAAUGCAGGAUCCUCUUUGCUGACUCAGGAAUACUCCAUAUUUUAGACUACUGCCUCUACCAUUAACUAGCCCAGACAUUUGAAUGGCCUUGUAAACAGCUCACUGUCUAAUACUCGAAGGACAAGUAACAAUUUAUAUUGGAUGAGAGUGGUCAAGAAAUAUGAUUUCGUUAGUUUUAUUAUCUGUUUACUUCCUCUGGGGAAGGCAGACUGAUAAAAUUAUAUGGGCUGGUAAAUUUUUGGUACAUUAAUUGCAAGCUGCAUGACAAAAUUUGUUUUUCUGGCAACAAUCUGACAUUAUUAGUGGAAUUCCACACCAACAGGGCUUGUGAGCUUCCAUUUCAUCUUACUGUAACUUCAAUUUUAUGGCAAAAAAAGGUACAAAGUUUAAAUACCCCUUUCUAGUAAUGCCAAAGACAUACAGUGUUUUACAUUCUCUCCUUUAUAGGUAACAAAAUAAUGUUUAGCUCAGUAAGUACUGAAAUAAUGAGUGACCAAUUUGAAGGAUUUUUAGAUUAUUUAAUCUUUGCUUAUGUUGCUUUUUCACAUGCUUAAUGAUGGAAAUGAAAUGUUAAAUCAACAAAAUAAGAUCCAGUGUUUCAUAACAUUUUUAUAAGUUUGGUAAACUUUAGUCCCAUUAUAUACUUUUGGGGACAGUGUUAUAAAUCAGAAUUUUACGACAGUUUGCAGAACACUGAUUUGAAAGCUUCCUAUGCAAAAUGAGAAGGGGUUCAAAUAUAUUAAUUAUCAUUAAGUAUUAAAUAAUAGGCAUUAGAUGUCUAAUGUGAGUAUAAUUUCAUCCAAGCCAUCUCAGAAAGUCUAAAAGGUUGGCAGGGGGUCAGCUGAAGACCUCACUGGAGUGGGUCUUAAUUUUUAAAAAGUGUCUCACUACAUUUAAGACAUGUGACACAUUCCCAUUGGUAACAAUUGCUCACCAUGGCAUUGUCUCAAAAAAGACUAUGGUGGGGAGGGUGGCACAUUCCUAAUGGGAUGUACCUCUCCCCACUCCCCUUGCUUGAGAAGCACUACUCAAAAAUUUACCAGACCUUACAACUGUGAUAAAACUUGAAUGUGUAUGAUGAAUAAGGCCAUUCAGUUAACUUUACCUCCCUUUACCCAUUGAAGGGGUUCCUUUUCCAUUGCUCAGUUUUUAGAAAAUAAUUCUCAUCUUUUUUCUAAAGAAAUGAAUUUGUGGCUGGUCUGAAGGUAGUGAGUUAGCUCAAUUGAUUGUUCGCAGUCAGUUAUAGAUCAAGCUCCUUGUUCUACUCUUCCCCUCUUCUCACUACUGCACUUGACUAGUCUUAAAACAAAGAAAGAACGAAUGAAUGAAUGAAUCUGUGGCUGGAUGCAGUGGCUCAUGCCUGUAAUCCCAGCACUUUGGGAGGCUGAAGUGGGAGGACUGCUUGGGCCCAAGAAUUCAGGACCAGUCUGGGCAACAGAGCCAGACACUGUCUCUAUAAAAAAAAGUUAAAACUAGCUGGUUGUGGUGGUGCACACCUGUGGUCCCAGCUACUGUGGAGGGUGAUGUGGGAGGAUUGCUUGAACCCAGGAGUUGGAUGCUGCAGUGAGCUAUGAUUGCGCCAUUGCGCUCCAGACUGGGCAACAGGGCAAGACCCUGCCUCAAAAAAAAAAAAAAAAGAAUUUGUAAUUGUUGGUAGGAUGUUAUGGGAAAUUUAGAGGUCUUCUGAGUAUAAAGUGGUUUAAAUAUUUGGUCUGCUGAAGUCUUUCUGGAAGUGUUGUUCCCCCUGCUGCCCCGCCCAGUAGAAACUUGCUCAUAUGAGAGGUUCUGAGGUAGGUGCGGUGUAGUAGAAUGGCAUUGUCAGAUAUGUUCAAGAAACCCUUCAUUUGACACUAUUUUGUACCUUAUGGUACCCUUUAACAUUUUUUAAUUAAAAAAAAUAUUUUUUGAGACAGGGUCUUGUUCUGUUGCCCAGGCUGGAGUGUAGUGUUGCAAUCUUGGCUCACUGCAACCUCUGCCUGACAGGCUUCAGUGAUCUUUCCACCUCAGCCUCCUGAGUAGCUGGGACUACAGGUGCAUGCCACCAAGCCUGGCUAACUUUUUGUAGAGAUAGGGUUUUGCCAUGCUGCCCAGGCUGGCUUAGAAUUCCUGAAUUCAAGUGAUUUGUCUGCCUCAGGCUCCCAAAGUGCUGGGAUUACAGGCAUGAGCCACACUGCACCCAGUCCAUGCUACCCUUUUUAUAUGAAACACCUAUUAACACGGUACAACAACACUUCAAAACAUAUUAUUUGAAUUUCGGCCUCUGAUUUUCUAGUCAACAAUCCAUUAAGGCAAAGACCUGUUUCCAAACUCAGAUGUUCUCCAACUUACACUAAUGUCUGGUUUUCUUGAACUAUGUGAGAGAAAAAAAUAAACAGAAUUUAUUUAUUAUCAUAAAGUCAUCCUGUUUGCCACUUAAUUUGGUUAUGUUUUAUCUACCACACUGCAAAUAUGUUAAUUCACCAUGAGAAACAGAUCCCUGUACACAUGUGUAUCAGUAAAUCAUUCAAUGAAUAGUUAGUGCUUAGGAUGUAU